AGCAGAGAAGGCGGAAGCAGUGGCGUCCGCAGCUGGGGCUUGGCCUGCGGGCGGCCAGCGAAGGUGGCGAAGGCUCCCACUGGAUCCAGAGUUUGCCGUCCAAGCAGCCUCGUCUCGGCGCGCAGUGUCUGUGUCCGUCCUCUACCAGCGCCUUGGCUGAGCGGAGUCGUGCGGUUGGUGGGGGAGCCCUGCCCUCCUGGUUCGGCCUCCCCGCGCACUAGAACGAUCAUGAACUUCUGAAGGGACCCAGCUUUCUUUGUGUGCUCCAAGUGAUUUGCACAAAUAAUAAUAUAUAUAUUUAUUGAAGGAGAGAAUCAGAGCAAGUGAUAAUCAAGUUACUAUGAGUCUGCUAAACUGUGAAAACAGCUGUGGAUCCAGCCAGUCUGAAAGUGACUGCUGUGUGGCCAUGGCCAGCUCCUGUAGCGCUGUAACAAAAGAUGAUAGUGUGGGUGGAACUGCCAGCACGGGGAACCUCUCCAGCUCAUUUAUGGAGGAGAUCCAGGGAUAUGAUGUAGAGUUUGACCCACCCCUGGAAAGCAAGUAUGAAUGCCCCAUCUGCUUGAUGGCAUUACGAGAAGCAGUGCAAACGCCAUGCGGCCAUAGGUUCUGCAAAGCCUGCAUCAUAAAAUCAAUAAGGGAUGCAGGUCACAAAUGUCCAGUUGACAAUGAAAUACUGCUGGAAAAUCAACUAUUUCCAGACAAUUUUGCAAAACGUGAGAUUCUUUCUCUGAUGGUGAAAUGUCCAAAUGAAGGUUGUUUGCACAAGAUGGAACUGAGACAUCUUGAGGAUCAUCAAGCACAUUGUGAGUUUGCUCUUAUGGAUUGUCCCCAAUGCCAGCGUCCCUUCCAAAAAUUCCAUAUUAAUAUUCACAUUCUGAAGGAUUGUCCAAGGAGACAGGUUUCUUGUGACAACUGUGCUGCAUCAAUGGCAUUUGAAGAUAAAGAGAUCCAUGACCAGAACUGUCCUUUGGCAAAUGUCAUCUGUGAAUACUGCAAUACUAUACUCAUCAGAGAACAGAUGCCUAAUCAUUAUGAUCUAGACUGCCCUACAGCCCCAAUUCCAUGCACAUUCAGUACUUUUGGUUGCCAUGAAAAGAUGCAGAGGAAUCACUUGGCACGCCACCUACAAGAGAACACCCAGUCACACAUGAGAAUGUUGGCCCAGGCUGUUCAUAGUUUGAGCGUUAUACCCGACUCUGGGUAUAUCUCAGAGGUCCGGAAUUUCCAGGAAACUAUUCACCAGUUAGAGGGUCGCCUUGUAAGACAAGACCAUCAAAUCCGGGAGCUGACUGCUAAAAUGGAAACUCAGAGUAUGUAUGUAAGUGAGCUCAAACGAACCAUUCGAACCCUUGAGGACAAAGUUGCUGAAAUCGAAGCACAGCAGUGCAAUGGAAUUUAUAUUUGGAAGAUUGGCAACUUUGGAAUGCAUUUGAAAUGUCAAGAAGAGGAGAAACCUGUUGUGAUUCAUAGCCCUGGAUUCUACACUGGCAAACCCGGGUACAAACUGUGCAUGCGCUUGCACCUUCAGUUACCGACUGCUCAGCGCUGUGCAAACUAUAUAUCCCUUUUUGUCCACACAAUGCAAGGAGAAUAUGACAGCCACCUCCCUUGGCCCUUCCAGGGUACAAUACGCCUUACAAUUCUUGAUCAGUCUGAAGCACCUGUAAGGCAAAACCACGAAGAGAUAAUGGAUGCCAAACCAGAGCUGCUUGCUUUCCAGCGACCCACAAUCCCACGGAACCCAAAAGGUUUUGGCUAUGUAACUUUUAUGCAUCUGGAAGCCCUAAGACAAAGAACUUUCAUUAAGGAUGACACAUUAUUAGUGCGCUGUGAGGUCUCCACCCGCUUUGACAUGGGUAGCCUUCGGAGGGAGGGUUUUCAGCCACGAAGUACUGAUGCAGGGGUAUAGCUUGCCCUCACUUGCUCAAAAACAACUACCUGGAGAAAACAGUGCCUUUCCUUGCCCUGUUCUCAAUAACAUGCAAACAAACAAGCCACGGGAAAUAUGUAAUAUCUACUAGUGAGUGUUGUUAGAGAGGUCACUUACUAUUUCUUCCUGUUACAAAUGAUCUGAGGCAGUUUUUUCCUGGGAAUCCACACGUUCCAUGCUUUUUCAGAAAUGUUAGGCCUGAAGUGCCUGUGGCAUGUUGCAGCAGCUAUUUUGCCAGUUAGUAUACCUCUUUGUUGUACUUUCUUGGGCUUUUGCUCUGGUGUAUUUUAUUGUCAGAAAGUCCAGACUCAAGAGUACUAAACUUUUAAUAAUAAUGGAUUUUCCUUAAAACUUCAGUCUUUUUGUAGUAUUAUAUGUAAUAUAUUAAAAGUGAAAAUCACUACCGCCUUGUGCUAGUGCCCUCGAGAAGAGUUAUUGCUCUAGAAAGUUGAGUUCUCAUUUUUUUAACCUGUUAUAGAUUUCAGAGGAUUUGAACCAUAAUCCUUGGAAAACUUAAGUUCUCAUUCACCCCAGUUUUUCCUCCAGGUUGUUACUAAGGAUAUUCAGGGAUGAGUUUAAACCCUAAAUAUAACCUUAAUUAUUUAGUGUAAACAUGUCUGUUGAAUAAUACUUGUUUAAGUGUUCCUUCUGCCUUGCUUACUUAUUUCCUUGAGGUUACGAAGUAGCAUCUUCCCCAGAGUUUAUAAUGCUGAGAACCACGUGGAUACCAACUGCUCAUUGUUAUGCUAUGUAACCCUUUUUGUCUAUUCAGUGCAGAGUGAAUUUCACAGCUCUGCAUAUGUCUUCAUUUGUUUAAUGCUUACAAGACAGGAGAUGCACACAUACAAUCAGCAACAUAAAAAUUAAAAGUGACCCAAGUAGUCAGCGCAUGUGGCAUCUCAUUGGUGGUGACAGAAGCUAUGUGAGCCAGAAGUUUUCAGCUCUUUUGAAUACCCUCUGGUUUAUUUCGAUUAAAAAGAACAAAAUUGAUUUCCUAAAAUCAGAAUUUUUUAAAACUUGGGAGAUGAUUGGAGAUACCUAGGAGGUCACCAAACUAGGAUUAGAAGUCACAGUGGUUGUAUCACAACUUAGCUUGAGUAUGUUGCUGUAGCCUAACAACUGCAGGUUCUGAGAAGGAUCCUGUAGAAUCCUGGAAGUAACCAGAUUUUCCUAAUAGGGAGAUGAUUUUUUUGUGUGCCAUCAUGUAUUUGUUAAAGGCCUAUAUAUAGAUAUAAAAUAUCGUGGAAUCUAGUUCUCAGGGAGACCCGCAACUAGUAUAAGCUUAUAAAGGAUCUAAAGAUCCAUCCACCAUUUAAAGUUGUCUGGUAAUGAGAGAUGACAUUGUAUCCCCCAGAGAGGCCAAAUCAGAGUCGCCAGCCAGCGUUCUAGAUCAGCCUUAAUUUCAAGAGAAAGCCAAGGACCUCAUCUGCAGGGGAGUGUGGUUUUCAGCCCCAGCGAGUGUCACUUUGAACUUUCCCUUUGCUUUUUUCUCUCUUCUCCCUCCCCACCCACCCUUAGGCUCCUGAUCUGGUGAGUUUGUUAUGGAGUGAAAAUAAAAGUCAAGCAGAGACCUUGUUUCCCGUGCCACCAUUAGUACCACAAGCUCAUGGCUAGUUACCACAUUACUUCCUGGCAGUUUGUGUCCCUCAGCUGUGCCUUCCAACCAGCGCCUGAGAAUCACUGCAUACCACCCUCUAGGUAGGGAAACCUACACUGCUGCUGUUCCUGUGAUUAUUUUACAAUGAAUAAAUAAUUGUCAAGUUCCAUUUAAAAACUGAACAGUAGUAUUUUUGUAUUUGCGUAGAAAAAGCCUGAAGGAAAUAUACUAAACUUUUUGUUGGCUUAUUUUCCUUUGCGCUUGCUUAUAUUUUUUACAUUUUCUACAAUAAAUGUGUACUUUUAUCGGAGAAAAAAAUUAAAUGUUGCCACAAAACAUUUAAUCUCCACGCCCCCAGCUCAAAAAAGGAAAUGAUAUUUAAAAGCUUCCUGGUCAGAUUUCUAUUAAAAGCACUGGCUGUGCAUUAGAUACAAAGAGGAGUCAUUUCCUGCCUUGGUGAUACUAUUUUUUUCUACUAACUCAAGAGUCUUUAUUAAAAAAAAAAGUUGUUUUGCCUAAUUUCAGCUUUUAGCAAGCUUCCCAUCUGUAAAAUGAUUUGGACCAGAUAUUUCUAGAGUCCCCUCCAGCCAUAACAUUCUGUCUCAAAUUAAGUUCCAACCAGCAGAACAAUGACAAUACUUAGGAAAGUAUUUUGCCAGUAUAAAAUGUCUUUAACUUACUCUUUGCUGACACUGAUACUUUCCUCUAAUUUAGUGUCUAUCAGCUGGGUCACAUCUUAAGUAAAAUGAGCAAUUUUAACCCCCAACAUUUGGCAUUUUGUCAUAAACCAGCCAGUUAUUUUAUGCUGGUCAUUCAUCUUGACUACAAAGUAGAAUAGUCAAGCUGUCAUUCCAAAUAGAAAACUUUUUACUUCAAUCAGAAUUAAGCCUUAACCUGGAAAGUUGGUUUCUUCCUUACAUUUUCCCAAUCUCCUACUCUAUUCUUAAACAUGCUAGUUUCACUCAGUUGGGUAUACAAGCCUUUGGGCUUUAUGUUGUAUGUUACUAACCACCUUUUACCAUAUUUAUCUUUUGGCAUCAUUCUGGGACAUUGCUAAAUUAAAAAAGAAAUUGUUUCCACUUUUUUCUGGAGAUGUUCAACUAAAGGUUGUUUUGUUUUGUUUUUUGUUUUGAGACAGUCUCACCCUGACGCUCAGGCUGGAGUGCAGUGGUGCAACCUCGGCUCACUGCAACCUCCACCUCCCGGGCUCAAGCCAUUCUCCUGCCUCAGCCUCCCAAGCAGCUGGGAUUACAGGCACCCGCCACCACGCCCAGCUAAUUUUUUUGUAUUUUGAGUAGAGACCGGGUUUCACCAUAUUGGCCAGUCUCGUCUGGAACUCCUGACCUCAGAUGAUCCGCCCGCCUCAGCCUCCCAAAGUGCUGGGAUUACAGGCAUGAGCCACCACGCCCAGCGUCCAACCCACUGUUGGAUGAAACUUGCUGCACGUCAUACAUUUUGCUGUUGGCAAACAAGUCUGAAUGUUGAUUUGAAGUUUGGUAGUUUAUUACUAUCUAUUGGCAGCAAAGACUGUUUAUUGGUAUACUACAAUAUGAUUUAACUUUUAUUUUGGGGAUAAAUAGUAGAAAAAAGUGAAACAGAAUGAAGGCAGGUGUUUUUUAUUCUAAUGAUGGAAUAAUACAGAGAUACUGGACGAUCUCUAGCAGUUAAUUAUUGUGACCCAUAUAAAAUUAUACAGGUCACAGUAUAAUUCUCUAUUACCGUUUUUACACCAGUAAGUCUUAGAUAAACUAAGCAUGCUUAUGAAUUAUGUAUACAGUUAGAAUGCAUUAUUUUUACAGAGGAACAAUUGCUUGUAUGUACUAACACUGUUCUCUUGGCUUGCCUCAAGUUCUACUCAUUAUUUUAUAUAAAAUACUAUUAGGCUGGGCACGGUGGCUCACGCCUAUAAUCCCAGCACUUUGGGAGGUGGAGGCUGGCGGAUUACUUGAAGCCAGGAGUUCGAGACCAGCCUGGCCAAAAUGGUGAAACCCCAUCUCUAUAAAAAUACAAAAAUUAGCCAGGUGUCAUGAUACAUGCCUGUAAUCCCAGCUUCUUGGGAGGCUGAGGCACGGGAAUCGCUUGAACCCGGGAAGCACAGGUUGCAGUGAGCCAAGAUCAUGCCACUGCACCCCCAGCCUGGGUGACAGAGUGCAACACUGUCUCACAAAACAAAACAAAAACAUCAGAUUCUGUUUGUGAUGCCUAGUUGCUUACAACCUAAACAGUGCAAUGCCUUAAGGAAAUGAAAAGGAGCCAUAAGUAGUCAUUUAUAUUUUUAUUUUGAAGUGUGCUUUUUCUAAACUCCCAGAUUGACAUGAUGGACUGUAAGUUAGUUUCUCUGUUUCUGUCUUUGUGCCUGUAGAGUGUACUUGGCACUUACAAAUUCCCAGUAUCCAGAAAGAUGAUCUGAUGAAAUCAAAUUGGAUGGAUCUUGGCAGACUGUGACACUCAAUUACAGCCUUCACUUUCAGUCAAAAACGGACACUUGGCAAGGAGGUGCCUGGUUGUUUCACUAAAUGUCACUUGUGUGUGUAAUAUUUUAAAGCUUUUUCCCCACAGGAAAUUCGGGUCAUAAAAUCCUGAAAAAUAAUUCUAGGUGGGAAAAGCAUUUUAGGAAAUGAGAGAUGUGGUGCUGCUUUUCUUCUCUCAGAGUGCUUUCUCAGCAGGACACUAGCCCUGCCUUUAAGAUGGGGAAGUUGGGGCAUGUGCCUCUGCUCUUACUGUCUGCAGCUCUGAAGGUAGGUGCUGUCCCACUCGGACAAUCGCCCAAGCAGCAGUGACCAUAGUUCUCUUCUAUGCAAGUCCCCAGGAGAAGGUAAACUGUGUGGAAUGGGGAUGUGUUCUGGUUGCUGCUGAAUCCCCUCUUCUUACCACAGUGCCUGGCACGUUGCACACACUCAAAUACGUAAUAAUGAACAUUUAUUGAAAGCAGCAGUUGAAGCUGACCAAUUUCUGGUACCUUGUCAUGUAAAUUUUAGAUGGUAAGGCGCAGAUGUUACUUUUUUUGCUUUUUUUCUUCAGCACUUGAUGAAAUUUCCCAAACAUGCAGAAAUGUUGAAAGACUUGUAUAGUGAACAUCUACGACCUAGAAUCUGCAGUAAUAUUAUGUUACAUUUGCUUUAUCACUUGAUAGAUGUUACUUUUAAUGAGACUUCAAGUUUGGUUUCUCUAAACAAAAUAUUCUAAAAUAACUGAACAACUUUAAUCAAUUUGUCUUAAGUUCUUUGGGGGAACUUGGGACAUUUGCUUUGUAACUGGAAUUGCAGCCCUCACGUUAAGCUAAUUUUAAACUUUGCAAAUUUGUUAUGCUGAAUUUCAGUCUUAUUUAUUUUGCCUGAAGGGGUAUUUUUUGUAAUGGAUUUAUUUGAAGGUCCUUGAUAAAUUGUGCAGAAUAUUCUCGUGUUCUUUUUGCACUUGAUAAAUUAUCUAAUUUCUGUGGUGAGAAUGUAAUUUGGGGCCUAUUUUGUUUAUACAAGCUUCCAGAAUUAUGUUCUCAGAGGGAUGAAAAGGUGUAAUUUAGCAUAUAGGUCACUAAAUUAGGAGCUAAGACACAUUUUCUCCUGACUGACCAUGGGUCAAUCAGUUUUGUCUUCGUGUCCUUUUCCUUGUAAAGUAGAAACUAGAAUUUGAAAUUUAAAUAUUAAAUAAUGGGUAACAUUCAUUAAUGUAUGACUCUAUUAAGAAAGACACUGUGAAUCCAGGGAGGAUUCUCAUAAUUCUGUAAACUGUAUGACAAGCUGUGGAAUGAAAUCUGACUUUUGAAAAUUGAAAGACAUCCAGUGGUCUUAUCACAAAGCCUGCUUUUCCUCAGAACUUAACUAUUGCCAUGGAAUUUGUAAGCAGUUAUCCUAAUCCAUCUGGACUCUGAAAAUGCAUCCUUUAUGAGAGGGAGUGAAUGCAAAGAUAAGGGUGGGGAAACACUAAUCAUGAAAAGAAUGAAAAUCAGUGUUCAGUUUUAAGAGCAGGUUGUAUUGAAGGAAGGGAUUAAAGGAAUUAUCCAGAUUUGAGGUGGCACAUCUUCCACCACUCCCUGCACCAUCAGCAUGCACGGAGCGCAUAAAACAAGCCCUGCUCCUAAUGGCAGUGAAACCUCGGAUGGCCUCCAUCAGGUCAAUACAACUGAAUUGCUGGGCUGACUUAAGAUUGAAGGACUCCAUUUUAGUAAGUAGAGAAGUGUGACCUUUCUCAACCCAGGUUGUGAAUGUGGAUUCACACUUAUCUCAAAAAGGCACCUGGAGUUUUAACUUUAUGUCAUGUCUCAGUACUGGUUGCAAGGUAUGACCAAAAGUGUUCCUUGAAUGGCACCUUUUUGAAUAUUAAUUUAGAAGAAAACAUGCCAGACUGACAUACUUACCCCCUCCGCACUGUUACUACUUCCUUACCAGCCCUAUGUACUGCAUCAAUGUCUACAAGAAAGCACUCUUCAUUAAAAUGAAAUAUAUAUAUUAAAA